AGUCGGCCUGCGCUCCUCAGCCUGGCGGUUCUACCUCCGAGGGUUCGCCCGCCCUUGGUUUUCCUUACACCUUAGCCUUUGGCUCCUUUGACCACUCGAAGCCCCACAGCGUGUUCCAGCGGACUUCACCAGCAGACCCAGAAGUGGUGGGUGAAACACUGCCUCUGUUCCUCCUUGAGCCUGUCGGGAGCUGCUGCCUGCCACCACCAUGUCUGCUGCAAAUCCUGAGACUCCAAACUCAACCAUCUCCAGAGAGGCCAGCACCCAGUCUUCAUCAGCUGCAGCUAGCCAAGGCUGGGUGUUACCAGAAGGCAAAAUCGUGCCAAACACUGUUUUUGUUGGUGGAAUUGAUGCUAGGAUGGAUGAAACUGAGAUUGGAAGCUGCUUUGGUAGAUACGGUUCAGUGAAAGAAGUGAAGAUAAUCACGAAUCGAACUGGUGUGUCCAAAGGCUAUGGAUUUGUUUCGUUUGUUAAUGACGUGGAUGUCCAGAAGAUAGUAGGAUCACAGAUACAUUUCCAUGGUAAAAAGCUGAAGCUGGGCCCUGCAAUCAGGAAACAAAAGUUAUGUGCUCGUCAUGUGCAGCCACGUCCUUUGGUAGUUAAUCCUCCUCCUCCACCACAGUUUCAGAACGUCUGGCGGAAUCCAAACACUGAAACCUACCUGCAGCCCCAAAUCACGCCGAAUCCUGUAACUCAGCACGUUCAGUCUGCUGCAAAUCCUGAGACUCCAAACUCAACCAUCUCCAGAGAGGCCAGCACCCAGUCUUCAUCAGCUGCAGCUAGCCAAGGCUGGGUGUUACCAGAAGGCAAAAUCGUGCCAAACACUGUUUUUGUUGGUGGAAUUGAUGCUAGGAUGGAUGAAACUGAGAUUGGAAGCUGCUUUGGUAGAUACGGUUCAGUGAAAGAAGUGAAGAUAAUCACGAAUCGAACUGGUGUGUCCAAAGGCUAUGGAUUUGUUUCGUUUGUUAAUGACGUGGAUGUCCAGAAGAUAGUAGGAUCACAGAUACAUUUCCAUGGUAAAAAGCUGAAGCUGGGCCCUGCAAUCAGGAAACAAAAGUUAUGUGCUCGUCAUGUGCAGCCACGUCCUUUGGUAGUUAAUCCUCCUCCUCCACCACAGUUUCAGAACGUCUGGCGGAAUCCAAACACUGAAACCUACCUGCAGCCCCAAAUCACGCCGAAUCCUGUAACUCAGCACGUUCAGGCUUACUCUGCUUAUCCACAUUCACCAGGUCAGGUCAUCACUGGAUGUCAGUUGCUUGUAUAUAAUUAUCAGGAAUAUCCUACUUAUCCCGAUUCAGCAUUUCAGGUCACCACUGGAUAUCAGUUGCCUGUAUAUAAUUAUCAGCCAUUUCCUGCUUAUCCAAGAUCACCAUUUCAGGUCACUGCUGGAUAUCAGUUGCCUGUAUAUAAUUAUCAGGCAUUUCCUGCUUAUCCAAAUUCACCAUUUCAAGUCGCCACUGGAUAUCAGUUCCCUGUAUACAAUUAUCAGCCAUUUCCUGCUUAUCCAAGUUCACCAUUUCAGGUCACUGCUGGAUAUCAGUUGCCUGUAUAUAAUUAUCAGGCAUUUCCUGCUUAUCCAAAUUCACCAUUUCAAGUCGCCACUGGAUAUCAGUUCCCUGUAUACAAUUAUCAGGCAUUUCCUGCUUAUCCAAAUUCACCAGUUCAGGUCACCACUGGAUAUCAGUUGCCUGUAUACAAUUAUCAGGCAUUUCCUGCUUAUCCAAAUUCACCAUUUCAAGUCGCCACUGGAUAUCAGUUCCCUGUAUACAAUUAUCAGGCAUUUCCUGCUUAUCCAAAUUCACCAGUUCAGGUCACCACUGGAUAUCAGUUGCCUGUAUACAAUUAUCAGGCAUUUCCUGCUUAUCCAAGUUCACCAUUUCAGGUCACCACUGGAUAUCAGUUGCCUGUAUAUAAUUAUCAGGCAUUUCCUGCUUAUCCAAGUUCACCAUUUCAGGUCACCACUGGAUAUCAGUUGCCUGUAUAUAAUUAUCAGGCAUUUCCUGCUUAUCCAAGUUCACCAUUUCAGGUCACCACUGGAUAUCAGUUGCCUGUAUAUAAUUAUCAGGCAUUUCCUGCUUAUCCAAGUUCACCAUUUCAGGUCACCACUGGAUAUCAGUUGCCUGUAUAUAAUUAUCAGGCAUUUCCUGCUUAUCCAAGUUCACCAUUUCAGGUCACCACUGGAUAUCAGUUGCCUGUAUAUAAUUAUCAGGCAUUUCCUGCUUAUCCAAAUUCAGCAGUUCAGGUCACCACUGGAUAUCAGUUCCAUGUAUACAAUUACCAGAUGCCACCGCAGUGCCCUGUUGGGGAGCAAAGGAGAAAUCUGUGGACCGAAGCAUACAAAUGGUGGUAUCUUGUCUGUUUAAUCCAGAGAAGAGACUGAUAAAUUCCGUUGUUACUCAAGAUGACUGCUUCAAGGGUAAAAGAGUGCAUCGCUUUAGAAGAAGUUUGGCAGUAUUUAAAUCUGUUGGAUCCUCUCAGCUAUCUAGUUUCAUGGGAAGUUGCUGGUUUUGAAUAUUAAGCUAAAAGUUUUCCACUAUUACAGAAAUUCUGAAUUUUGGUAAAUCACACUGAAACUUUCUGUAUAACUUGUAUUAUUAGACUCUCUAGUUUUAUCUUAACACUGAAACUGUUCUUCAUUAGAUGUUUAUUUAGAACCUGGUUCUGUGUUUAAUAUAUAGUUUAAAGUAACAAAUAAUCGAGACUGAAAGAAUGUUAAGAUUUAUCUGCAAGGAUUUUUAAAAAAUUGAAACUUGCAUUUUAAGUGUUUAAAAGCAAAUACUGACUUUCAAAAAAGUUUUUAAAACCUGAUUUGAAAGCUAACAAUUUUGAUAGUCUGAACACAAGCAUUUCACUUCUCCAAGAAGUACCUGUGAACAGUACAAUAUUUCAGUAUUGAGCUUUGCAUUUAUGAUUUAUCUAGAAAUUUACCUCAAAAGCAGAAUUUUUAAAACUGCAUUUUUAAUCAGUGGAACUCAAUGUAUAGUUAGCUUUAUUGAAGUCUUAUCCAAACCCAGUAAAACAGAUUCUAAGCAAACAGUCCAAUCAGUGAGUCAUAAUGUUUAUUCAAAGUAUUUUAUCUUUUAUCUAGAAUCCACAUAUGUAUGUCCAAUUUGAUUGGGAUAGUAGUUAGGAUAACUAAAAUUCUGGGCCUAAUUUUUUAAAGAAUCCAAGACAAACUAAACUUUACUGGGUAUAUAACCUUCUCAAUGAGUUACCAUUCUUUUUUAUAAAAAAAAUUGUUCCUUGAAAUGCUAAACUUAAUGGCUGUAUGUGAAAUUUGCAAAAUACUGGUAUUAAAGAACGCUGCAGCUUUUUUAUGUCACUCAAAGGUUAAUCGGAGUAUCUGAAAGGAAUUGUUUUUAUAAAAACAUUGAAGUAUUAGUUACUUGCUAUAAAUAGAUUUUUAUUUUUGUUUUUUAGCCUGUUAUAUUUCCUUCUGUAAAAUAAAAUAUGUCCAGAAGAGGCAUGUUGUUUCUAGAUUAGGUAGUGUCCUCAUUUUAUAUUGUGACCACACAGCUAGAGCACCAGAGCCCUUUUGCUAUACUCACAGUCUUGUUUUCCCAGCCUCUUUUACUAGUCUUUCAGGAGGUUUGCUCUUAGAACUGGUGAUGUAAAGAAUGGAAGUAGCUGUAUGAGCAGUUCAAAGGCCAAGCCGUGGAAUGGUAGCAAUGGGAUAUAAUACCUUUCUAAGGGAAACAUUUGUAUCAGUAUCAUUUGAUCUGCCAUGGACAUGUGUUUAAAGUGGCUUUCUGGCCCUUCUUUCAAUGGCUUCUUCCCUAAAACGUGGAGACUCUAAGUUAAUGUCGUUACUAUGGGCCAUAUUACUAAUGCCCACUGGGGUCUAUGAUUUCUCAAAAUUUUCAUUCGGAAUCCGAAGGAUACAGUCUUUAAACUUUAGAAUUCCCAAGAAGGCUUUAUUACACCUCAGAAAUUGAAAGCACCAUGACUUUGUCCAUUAAAAAAUUAUCCAUAGUUUUUUUAGUGCUUUUAACAUUCCGACAUACAUCAUUCUGUGAUUAAAUCUCCAGAUUUCUGUAAAUGAUACCUACAUUCUAAAGAGUUAAUUCUAAUUAUUCCGAUAUGACCUUAAGGAAAAGUAAAGGAAUAAAUUUUUGUCUUUGUUGAAGUAUUUAAUAGAGUAAGGUAAAGAAGAUAUUAAGUCCCUUUCAAAAUGGAAAAUUAAUUCUAAACUGAGAAAAAUGUUCCUACUACCUAUUGCUGAUACUGUCUUUGCAUAAAUGAAUAAAAAUAAACUUUUUUUCUUCAAAUGUG